ACGGCGCCGUAAAGCAGCUCGGCCGAGCAGACUGCUGCGGUUCCUGGUGAGACCCUACCCACCCCCCUGCCCGCGCCGGGCCUCGUCCGCUCCCCGGCCCCUUCCCCGCGGGCGUGUGGGUCCCGGGCUGGGGUCUCGGCGUCCGCGAUCCCGAGCCCGCUCGCUUCGGCCCCCCUCAGGAGGCUGCGAGGAGGGUGGGUUUCUCCCCAGUGUAGAGGGUGGCGGCGGCAUGGAGGCGCGCUUCACGCGCGGGAAGUCGGCGCUGCUGGAGCGCGCGCUGGCGCGGCCGCGCACCGAGGUGAGCCUGAGCGCCUUCGCACUGCUGUUCUCCGAGCUGGUACAGCACUGCCAGAGCCGCGUCUUCUCCGUGGCCGAGCUGCAGUCGCGCCUGGCCGCGCUGGGCCGCCAGGUGGGCGCGCGCGUGCUGGAUGCGCUGGUGGCGCGCGAAAAGGGUGCCCGGCGUGAGACCAAGGUGCUAGGCGCGUUGCUCUUCGUCAAGGGCGCCGUGUGGAAGGCGCUCUUCGGCAAGGAGGCGGACAAGCUGGAGCAGGCCAACGAUGACGCGCGCACCUUCUACAUCAUCGAGCGCGAGCCGCUCAUCAACACCUACAUCUCCGUGCCCAAGGAGAACAGCACGCUCAACUGCGCCAGCUUCACGGCGGGCAUCGUGGAGGCGGUGCUCACACACAGCGGCUUCCCUGCCAAGGUCACGGCGCACUGGCACAAGGGCACCACGCUCAUGAUCAAGUUCGAGGAGGCAGUCAUCGCUCGAGACCGGGCCCUGGAGGGCCGCUGACCCUGCCGGAGAUAAAGGAUACAGAGAGCCCCUCCCCACGUGUGUCUUGUGUCUUGUGUGGCGGCCUUAGAUCCACUCAGUACCUUGAGCCACAGCCCUGCCCCAGGCUGGGGAGGGAGGCCAGGUCCGAAUGUGUUUACAGUAGAGUGGGGGCGGGUCUGGCCAUAGGGUUGGGGGGUUGAGUGAGACCAGGAGUGGUGGGGAGAAAUAAACCCGGCAAAAGGAGUUGGUGGGAAAUGCUGGCAGGUUCUGGAAUCACGGUUGGAGGCUGUCUGCAGGCUGGAGGGGGCAUGGGGUCCUGGGAGACGCAUCAGGCUGAGACAGACGCCUUUAGACUGGGGGUGGGCAAACUGCGCAAAGUGCCAGAUGGGCAAUAUUUUAUGCCAUGUGGUCUUUAUUAUUAUUUUUUUUAUUUGUUGAGAUAGAGUCUUGCUCUGUCGCCCAGGCUGGAGUGCAGUGGCACCAUCUCACCUCACUGCAAACCUCCACCUUGGGUUCACGUGAUUCUCCUGCCUCAGCUUCCCAAGUAGCUGGGAUUACAGGUGCCUCCCACCACACCCGGCUAAUUUUUGUAUUUUUAGUAGAGAUGGGGUUUCACCAUGUUGGUCAGGCUGGUCUCGAACUCCUCAUCUCAGGUGAUCCGCCCACUUCAGCCUCCCAAAGUGCUGGGAUUACAGGCGUGAGCCACUGCUGUGCCGCCAUGUGCUCUUGCCCCAUUACUCCGCUGAUGUACUGAAUGCAACCACAGACAACAUGUAAAGGAGUGGGUGUCACCGUGUGCCUAGAAAACAGGCAGAGGGAGAUUGUUUGCCUUCUUCCCUCAUUUAUUAUAUUUUUCAGAGACAGGGUUUUGUUCUGUCGCCCAGGCUGGAGUGCAGUGGCAGCAUCUCGGCUUCGGCUCACUGCAAGCUCCGCCUCCCGGGUUCAUGUCAUUCUCCUGCCCCAGCCUCCCGAGUAGCUGGAACUACAGGUGCCCACCACCACACCUGGCUAAUUUUUCGUAUUUUUAGUAGAGACGGGGUUUCACCAUGUUAGCCAGGAUGGUCUCGAUCUCCUCACCUCGUGAUCUGCCCACCUCGGCUUCCCAAAGUGCUGGGAUUACAGGCGUGAGCCAUGGCGCCCAGCCAUGCCCAGCUAAUUUUUAAAAAAUUUUUGUAGAGAUGGGGGCUCUUAUUAGGUUGCCCAGGCUGGUCUCAAACUCUUGGCCUCAAGCAAUCCUUCCACCUUGGCCUCCGUAAGUGCUGGGGUUACAGGCGUGAGCCAAAUCAAAGUGUGUUCUGUAGAUCAGCAGUAGCAGCAUCAACUGGGAGUUGGUCCAUAAUGCAGUCUCAGGCCCACCCCAGAGCUGCUGAAUCUGAGGGUGCAUUUUAGCGAGGCCCCCAGGGGAUUCCUGGGGACCUUAGAUUGAGAUGCAGGCUUUAGGGUAUCAGAAUCACCAGGAGGGGCCACGUGCGGUGGCUCACGCCUGUAAUCCCAGCACUUUGGGAGGCUGAGGCAGGUGGAUCACCUGAAGUCAGGAGUUCGAGACCAGCCUGGCUAACAUGGCAAAACCCCGUCUCUACUAAAAAUAGAAAACAUUAGCCGGGUGUGGUGGCACAUGCCUGUAAUCCCAGCUACUUGGGAGGCUGAGGCAGGAGAAUCGCUCCAACCCGGGAGGUGGAGGUUGCAGUGAGCCGAGAUUGCACCAUUGCACUCCAGCCUGGGCAACAAGAGCGAAACUCCAUCUAAAAAACAAAAAGGUCAGGCGCGGUGGCUCACGCCUAUAAUCCCAGCACUUUGGGAGGCCGAGGCAGGCGGAUCACGAGGUCAGGAGUUCGAGCCAGCCUGGCCAAUAUGGUGAAACCCUGUCUCUACUAAAAAUACAAAAAUUAGCUGGGCAUGGAGGUGCAUUCCUGUAGUCCCAGCUACCUAAUUUUUUGUAUUUUUAGUAGAGAUGAGGUUUCACUGUGUUGGCCAGUCUGGUCAAUACUUUAAAGUUAAUUUUAAAGUCCAGGAUGAUACAAACACAUUUCCCUUGUUAAAAAAAUUUUAAAAUAAGUGGGGUGCAGUGGUGCACACCUGGAGUCCCAGCUAUUCAGGAGGCCGAGGCAGAAGGAUCGCUUGAGGCCAGGGGUUGGUGUCCAGCCUGGGCAACAUAGUGAGACCUUGUCUAAAAGAAUUUGAAAUAAGGCCAGGCGUGGCGACUUAUGUCUGUAAUCCCAGCACUUUGAGAGGCCGAGGUGGGCAGAUCACUUGAGGCCGGAAGUUUGAGACCAACCUGGUCAACAUGGCAAAACCCAUCUUUACUAAAAAUACAAAAAUUAGCUGGGCGUGGUGGCAGGCACCUGUAAUCCCAGCUACUUGGGAGGCUAAGGCAGGAGGAUCACUUAAACCUGGGAGGCGGAGGUUGAAGUGAGCCAAGAUCACACCACUGGCACUCCAGCCUGAGCAACAGAGUGAGACCCUGUCUUAAAAAAGAAAAAAAAAGUAAUGUAUUACACCUCAGGCAAUUUUCCUUUCCCUUUUUGUUCACCACACUUGGUUCCUGAUAACUCCUCCUCUCCCCCAAGGAAAGUUCUUCCAGAUUUUUUGGGGGAACCAUGAUCCAAUCUUCCCUGCUUCCUUUCCACCGCCCCCCAGAAUGUGAACAGACAGGUCUGUUCAGAAAAGGAACUGCAGGGACUGUCAGCUGGGCUCCCCUCACUGGUUAUGAGAAGGGCCAAAGGGGUCGGUGUCACCUCUAGAUUUGUUUAGGAUGCUCUGUUGGACUGCCUGGUGGACCAGGGCUGAGGGCUUGGUCAGGGCAGUCUCAGCCAUCCUAGCAAGAGGCAUUGAGCAGGGUGGGCUUCAGCACACUGGGGAGAAGGUGGCGUCUCUAGGAUGAAUGAAACCAUUGAGCAACCACCACACAUAGCCCCAGGGCUGAUCCUGGAAUAGCUGUUGGCUGUUGGAGGUGGAGGGAGGCGCCGGGAGAGGGCUUGGGCAGGAUGAUAGCCUGAAUCUGGAAUGAGGGGGAGGCGUCUAGGGGGCCAGCAGAUGCACAGGUCUUGGGGUUUGGGGUCUGGAGUUCUGGAGGGAGGUCUGGGCGUCUGCACAGACACAGAAACCACAGUCCUGGAUGGGGGACGGAGGGAGGGGAACAUGGUGUCUGAGAAGCUGGAUUUCAGAGCAAAAUGCAGGACGCUUUGGGCUAAGCAGCCCCAGGCAGGUCCUCUGAGACCCUGGCGAGAGGGGCUUCCAGGGCCGGCCAGGGCAGGGGCCAUUCUUCUGUCCAGAGGCGGGGCUGUGAGGGAUGUCAGAGAAAUCGGGAGGGAGGAAGAGGGGCUGCGGGAAUUUGUAAGCUGGGAGUGCAGGGCCCAGGGUCUGUUCCCACGCCCCAUCCCCACCGGCCACCGAGGGUGAGUUAGGGGGCUUGAGGAGAAGGGAAAACGUUUGAACAAGCUGUAGGGUUAUGAGGCUGGGCCCGGGGUUGGGGCAAGGGAGGAUGAAGAGAAAGAAGAGCCUGUGGUUCGGCAGCUUCUGAUCACAGCAGCUCUAACUUACGGUGCUCUGGGCUGCAAGGAAGGUCUUCCCCUGGACCCUCCAGGUGGGUGGGUGAGAGGAAGAGGAGGAGGAGGAGCCAGGCACCAGCCCUUGGUGAGCUGGGCAAGCAGCAUCAGCUCAUUUCACAGGCAGGUUCCAAAAGAAGUCAUGUGCCCAUGGUCACACAGAUUAAUUAUUAUUAUUAUUAUUAUUUAGAGAUGGAGUCUCACUCUGUCGCCCAGGCUGGAGUGCAGUGGUGCGAUCUCAGAUCUCAGCCUCCUGGGUUCAAGCAAUUCUCCUGCUUCAGCCUCCUGAAUAGUUGGGACUAUAGGCAUCCGCCACCACACCCAGCUAAUUUUUGUAUUUUUAGUGGAGACGGGGUUUCACCAUGUUGGCCAGGCUGGUCUGGAACUCCUGACCUCAAGUGAUCUGCCCGCCUUGGCCUCCCAAAGUGCUAGGAUUACAGGCGUGAGCCACCGCACCUGGCUGGCUUUUUCUCUUUUCUUCUUCUUUUUUUUUGAGACAGGUUCUCACUGUCGCCCAGGCUGAGAGCAGGGGCACAAUCCUCCCACCUCGGCCUCCCAAGCAGCUGGGACCAAGUUGCCCAUCACUACACCUCUAGUUUUUGUAUUUUUUGUAGAGAUGGGGCCUCACUAUGUUGCCCAGGCUGGCCUCAAACUCCUGAACUCAAGCAGUCCUCCCACCUCAGCCUCCCAAAGCGCUGGGAUGACAGGCAUGAGCCACUGUGCGCAGCUGGCUUUGGCCUUUUAUCUGAGCUGGAGGAAACUUCUGGAAAGGGGGCAGUGAAGAGAGAGCCCCGGGCGGAGGUGACUGCUCCAGUCGAGGCAGUGGCAGAAGGGGUGAGCAGUGAGUGAUUGUGAGCGCCGUUUGACAGCAGAGCCCACUGGCAUUUCUUAUGGUCUUGGACCUGGAGGUGUUGUCAGGGGAAAGGGAAGAGGUGCAAUGACCCCAGUGUUGGCCUGAGCCACUGGUAGAGGAGUGUGGAGAGGGGACCCUGUGCUCCUGGCCUCCCUCCCGUGGCCUCCGGCAUGGGUCGACCUUGGCCGAGCGUGAGGCUGGUGCCACCUCAGCCUCCCAGACCCUGAGUAGGGUUAACACCUCCAGACCCGAAAUGGCCUCCGGUUGACCGGGCCCACUCCCCAUCAGCCUGUCCAGCCAGCCAGCACUUACUGAGUGCCUUCUGUGUACUAAGCCCUGCUCUGGGUACUUCCAUGAGUCAACUCACGCCCUCCCGGCCUCAGGGUGAUCCACCGCCUUCCCCUACAGUAUUCCAAGGGGCCAUUGGACCUCAGAGGCUUCAUGUCCUGCACAUUCUCCGUGUCAUAGAGCAGGAAAAAAUAAAAACGGGAGAUCGAAUUCUA